GUCCCCGUCCAGAGUCCUCUGUGGUCCCUGCUGCCACCAUGGCCACUCACCGCCUCGUGAUGGUCCGGCACGGCGAGAGCACAUGGAACCAGGAGAACCGUUUCUGUGGCUGGUUCGAUGCAGAGCUGAGUGAAAAGGGGACCGAGGAGGCCAAGCGGGGAGCCAAGGCCAUCAAGGAUGCCAAGAUGGAGUUUGACAUCUGCUACACGUCAGUGCUGAAGCGGGCCAUCCGCACCCUCUGGGCCAUCCUGGACGGCACGGACCAGAUGUGGCUGCCUGUGGUGCGCACUUGGCGCCUCAAUGAGCGGCAUUACGGGGGCCUCACAGGCCUCAACAAGGCAGAAACGGCCGCCAAGCACGGGGAGGAGCAGGUGAAGAUCUGGAGGCGCUCCUUCGACAUCCCGCCGCCCCCGAUGGACGAGAAGCACCCCUACUACAACUCCAUUAGCAAGGAGCGUCGGUACGCAGGCCUGAAGCCCGGGGAACUCCCCACCUGCGAGAGCCUCAAGGACACCAUUGCCCGGGCCCUGCCCUUCUGGAACGAGGAGAUUGUUCCCCAGAUCAAGGCCGGCAAGCGAGUGCUCAUUGCAGCCCACGGGAACAGCCUGCGGGGCAUUGUCAAGCACCUGGAAGGGAUGUCAGACCAGGCGAUCAUGGAGCUGAACCUGCCCACGGGGAUCCCCAUUGUGUAUGAGCUGAACAAGGAGCUGAAGCCCACCAAGCCCAUGCAGUUCCUGGGUGAUGAGGAAACGGUGCGGAAGGCCAUGGAGGCUGUGGCUGCCCAGGGCAAGGCCAAGUGAGGGGUGGGCUUGGGCAAUAAAGGCACCUCCCCCAACA